UCUCUGUUGAUGGACACUCGGGCUGUUACUACUUUUUCAGCAUUUUGAUUAAAGCUGCAAUAAACAUUGAUACACAAAUGUCUGUUUGAGUUCCUGUUUUCAGUUCUUUGGGGUCUAUACGUAGGAGUGUGCUAGGUAUUUUAUGUUUUAUAUAUAUUUUACUGCAAUUAAAAAAUAAAUAUAUAAAAGACUGGCCUGUGUGAAGACCUCGGGAGGUAAGAAUGGCUGGAGCAACAGCUGGAUCAUGAAGGGCUGGGCACGCCCUUGUUUAGGAGUUGGUUUUAUCCUGAAAGCAGGAACCAUGGAGGGAUUUUGAAUGAGGGGGUCAUAAAGUUAGAUUUGCAUUUUAGAGCGAUGUAAACUGCCAUUACCAGGAAGAAUAUUAGACAGAAUAUUCACCUGCUAGUCCCAAGGAUUUGGGUCAGGGCAGGCCUCUGUCUGUGCAGAAACAAAGUCUGGUAAAAGGGCAGUUACGGAAAGGGCUUAUACUAAGCAUAUUUUUCUAGUGUAGCUGAACAACUCAACCAUGAUAACCUGCUGGAAGUGAUGCAAGAAAUAUCUUGAACGACCUAAAGUACCGGCCAUAUUUUUUUCUUAUGUCUGGAAAUCUCAAAAGCACAUGCUCACUUCUAUAAUUGUAAUCAUUUGAUCAGUGUGUACUGUAAGGAUUGAAAUGCCAAUAUGUUUUGCUUCCUUGGUAGCUGAGAGAUAACCUGCAAAAACAUGUUGUUCUUGUUCUGGAAAUGGCUCUUUCUAUUACCUUUAUUUCUCCAUUUAUCUUUUUUUCUAGGAAGUACCUGUAGACCAGGAAUACUGGGCCAGAAGAAAAAAAUACUGUCUAGUUUAGCAAAUUGCAGAAUGGACAGCACUGAAUGUUGGAACAUAAAAUUUUUAAAAGGUUUUGGCUUGUGAUCAACCAGGAGGGAAACAUGGUUACUGCUCGCCAGGAACCUCGCCUGGUCCUGAUUUCCCUGACCUGCGAUGGUGACACCCUGACUCUCAGUGCAGCCUACACAAAGGACCUACUACUGCCUAUCAAAACGCCCACCACAAAUGCAGUGCACAAGUGCAGAGUGCACGGCCUGGAGAUAGAGGGCAGGGACUGUGGCGAGGCCACCGCCCAGUGGAUAACCAGCUUCCUGAAGUCACAGCCCUACCGCCUGGUGCACUUCGAGCCUCACAUGCGACCGAGACGUCCUCAUCAAAUAGCAGACUUGUUCCGACCCAAGGACCAGAUUGCUUACUCAGACACCAGCCCAUUCUUGAUCCUUUCUGAGGCGUCGCUGGCGGAUCUCAACUCCAGGCUAGAGAAGAAAGUUAAAGCAACCAACUUCAGGCCCAAUAUUGUAAUUUCAGGAUGCGAUGUCUAUGCAGAGGUAACACUAUGCCCCUUUGGAUCUUUCCUUGGAUUUGACUUCUUUUUUAAGGAUUCUUGGGAUGAGCUUCUUAUUGGUGACGUGGAACUGAAAAGGGUGAUGGCUUGUUCCAGAUGCAUUUUAACCACAGUGGACCCAGACACCGGUGUCAUGAGCAGGAAGGAACCGCUGGAAACACUGAAGAGUUAUCGCCAGUGUGACCCUUCAGAACGAAAGUUAUAUGGAAAAUCACCACUCUUUGGGCAGUAUUUUGUGCUGGAAAACCCAGGGACCAUCAAAGUGGGAGACCCUGUGUACCUGCUGGGCCAGUAAUGGGAACCGUAUGUCCUGGAAUAUUAGAUGCCUUUUAAAAAUGUUCUCAAAAAUGACAACACUUGAAGCAUGGUGUUUCAGAACUGAGACCUCUACAUUUUCUUUAAAUUUGUGAUUUUCACAUUUUUCGUCUUUUGGACUUCUGGUGUCUCAAUGCUUCAAUGUCCCAGUGCAAAAAGUAAAGAAAUAUAGUCUCAAUAACUUAGUAGGACUUCAGUAAGUCACUUAAAUGACAAGACAGGAUUCUGAAAACUCCCCGUUUAACUGAUUAUGGAAUAGUUCUUUCUCCUGCUUCUCCGUUUAUCUACCAAGAGCGCAGACUUGCAUCCUGUCACUACCACUCGUUAGAGAAAGAGAAGAAGAGAAAGAGGAAGAGUGGGUGGGCUGGAAGAAUAUCCUAGAAUGUGUUAUUGCCCCUGUUCAUGAGGUACGCAAUGAAAAUUAAAUUGCACCCCAAAUAUGGCUGGAAUGCCACUUCCCUUUUCUUCUCAAGCCCCGGGCUAGCUUUUGAAAUGGCAUAAAGACUGAGGUGACCUUCAGGAAGCACUGCAGAUAUUAAUUUUCCAUAGAUCUGGAUCUGGCCCUGCUGCUUCUCAGACAGCAUUGGAUUUCCUAAAGGUGCUCAGGAGGAUGGUUGUGUAGUCAUGGAGGACCCCUGGAUCCUUGCCAUUCCCCUCAGCUAAUGACGGAGUGCUCCUUCUCCAGUUCCGGGUGAAAAAGUUCUGAAUUCUGUGGAGGAGAAGAAAAGUGAUUCAGUGAUUUCAGAUAGACUACUGAAAACCUUUAAAGGGGGAAAAGGAAAGCAUAUGUCAGUUGUUUAAAACCCAAUAUCUAUUUUUUAACUGAUUGUAUAACUCUAAGAUCUGAUGAAGUAUAUUUUUUAUUGCCAUUUUGUCCUUUGAUUAUAUUGGGAAGUUGACUAAACUUGAAAAAUGUUUUUAAAACUGUGAAUAAAUGGAAGCUACUUUGACUAGUUUCAGAUCUUACUAACUUCUUGGCACAAAGUUAGACUGUGAAAGCUGACUGAGGCUGGGCACAGGGGCUCAUGCCUGUAAUUCCAGCACUUUGGGAGGCCAAGGUGGGAGAAUGGCUUGAGCCCAGGAGUUUGAGACCAGCCCAGAAAAUAUAAUGGGAUCCUGUCGCUACAAAAUGUUUUUAAAAUGCACUCGGUGUGGUGGUGUGUGCCUGCAGUCCUGGCUAUGGCUACUCGGGAGGAUGAGGUAGAAGGAUUGGUUGAGCCCAGGAGCGGGAGAUUGAGGCUGCAGUGAGUUAUGAUUGCACCACUACACUCCAGCCUGAGUGAUAGAGUGAGACCCUAUCUCUAAAAAAGAAACAGGAAAAAAAAAGAAAGCUGACUGAGGUGAAUGGGCAAAGCCAGUAAUUCUGACACCUGACCACAGCUGGGUCUUCUGCAUAAUGGACCUCCUCACCCACAGCCUCCCAGGCAAGCACCCAUGUUUGAAGGACUAUCAAGUCAACAUGCUUUUUACCAAAAGCUGCACAUUUUUCACUUUGAUUUUAUAAAAGAGGUCAGUAAUCGCUGAAAUCUAGCUGAGCCCUGAAGUAAAGUUCUGAGCAAAGAGGUGCAUGUGCUUGUUUUAUGGUUGGUGAAUUAUUACAGUUUGUUUUCUGCAUGCUUGGCAUGAGGUGAAUAAUUACAUCAAUUUUCCAGAGAACCUGGGCCAUCACCUUCCCCAACAAGUCCAGUUGAUGUUGAAACUACAGAUAGAUUGAGACAAAGCGAAGUGUUCAGCAAGUAGCAUUACUAAUGGGACCGGGGGACCCGUGGGAGAGUGAGUGUACACAGGAUUUAGGAAACCAUGUGAAUAUGGGCUCUCUGGGAAUAGCCAAUAGGUAGGGAGCAAUCAGAAACCCAAGGUUUGGUGGCUCUUCCUAGGUAUUUAUAAUUAGUGGCAAGUGAAAGCCUUAGUCCUGAAUUUCUAACCACUUGUAAGAACUAACAGCCACUUCUCUGUGCCCCGUCCGGGCAGUAACCAUCAUUCUCCAUGGACAGGCUCUCGGGGUAGCUAGCUCUGCAGGGCAGCACCCACGUGGAAGGGAGCACCCAGAAACCCUCCUCACUGGGCAGACCUGUCCUUCUGUGCCUCACAGUGUGAGGAAGAUUCCUGUUUGAAGAGAGAAGUUCCAGUGACCUCUAGAAUCUCAGAGUAGUUGCCAAGCUUUCUGUCAGUGAGAUUUAAAGGCCAUUUACUUGUGUUUAUUUUAUAUUUAAUGAGUUGGUUAAUGCCAGAGACAAAGCUGAUAUCCCAUUUAUUUUGGAUACUGAGCAUUUGCACACUAUUCCACUUGAAAUAUAGAAUCAGGAAUGUAGGCCAUCCCAGACUUUCAGAUCUUACAACAGCAAAUGACAGAUGUUUGAGAUCAGGCCAAAAUAUCCACCCUCGGUGGGCAUCUCCUCUGUGUGGCAACUUAUGCUGCAGCCACAGUGGGGAGUCACAAACUCAGAGCUGGAGGUCUUGAAAAGGACAAUGUGGGCCAGGCUCCGGAGGGGCUGCCUAAAGGCUUGCUUUUGUGACUCUCCUGCAGAAAAUGUUAGAAACUUCCAACCGAAAGACGAGGGCAGCAACUUAUACACACGAAGGCAGAAAGAAAUUGGGGAAGGGGAGGCUGUUGGAAUUCAGGCCGUUGUCCUAUAGGGAGAAAUACUCCUCCUCUCCUUCUCCCUUUACUGAUAACGGGGCAUGGUGAGGAGAUGAGCUUGUGAGGGUCUGCCAGUUUGGUAAGAGUGCAUGGGGAGGUUGGGUAAAUUAGACUAGCCAAAUGGGACUUCGGGAAACCAUUUAUGAGGCUGUCACCAACAGUGAUGGCAGGCUGAAAUUCCAGGCAAGUGCUCCCAGCAUUCCAAGAGUGUAUCAAAUUAAAGCAACCCAUGAUGGUGGAGAACAGAUACAUUAAAGUUCCUUGAAAAUGACAGAGUGGCUCUCAGACCAGACCUUGAUUGUGGGUAUAAUCGGAGUGUUGCUACCACACCCUAACACUGCAUUUCCCGUGUUUUAUUGGUCCAUGGAAUUCUGAAAGUUUGCCUUUCGGGAUGCUUCUAAAAACAAUUCCAUGGACCAGUAAGUUUGGAAAGUCCUGCGUGCCUCACUUCUCUUCAAAGGCAAAAGGCUCUGGAGAGGCCUUCAUGAAGACAUCUGUGUUUAAUGCUGCCCUUCCCAAAGGUCUGUUUUUGACUGUCUUUUGAGAAAUGAUCCUCUGAUCUCUAGGCAGAAUGCCAGUGAGCCAAGGAAUCCCAGUUAGCAGGAGGGGUGCACUCAUGGGAAGACUGAAGAAGUUAAAAGUUCCCGCCAAGUGAAGGAGACCUAUCUUGGGACACUUCCCCUUGUCCUCUCCCUUGCCCCUCUUGCUGGAGUAAAAGGAUGGAACUGGGACUUGAUAGGUUAAAGGAGGUGUGGAGAAGUGUCUUAGACCAGCUCUCCUGUUGUGGGCCUUAGGGAGAAGCACUCUCUUUCUUCGGGAUCAUUUUCCAAACAUGCAUUUUUGGAUGGAUAGGGUGGAUCAGGGUGAGGGAAGGGAAACCAAACUCUCUCUAACCUUGCCCUUACAGCAAUACCUGUGAUGUAAGUUACAAAACCACCUGUGAUGAAAGUGCUCCAGGAUGCUUCAUGCACCAGGGAGGGGUGCCCUGUUUCUCUUCUGCUAGCUUCUCCUUUCUUUUUUUUUUUUCUUCUUUUUUUUGAGACAGUGUCUCACUCUGUUGCCAGGCUGGAGUGCAGUGGUGAGAUCUCAGCUCACUGCAGCCUCUGCCUCCCAGGUUCAAGCAAUUCUUCUGCCUCAGCCUCCCGAGUAGCUGGUGUGUCUGGAGUUGGUUCCUUCUGGUGGGUUCUUGGUCUCGCUGACUUCAAGAAUGAAGCCACAGACCUUCGCAGUGAGUGUUACAGCUCUUAAAGGUGGCACGGACCCAAAGUGAGCAGUAGCAAGAUUUAUUGUGGAGAGCGAAAGAACAAAGCUUCGGAAGGGGACCCAAAUGGGCUGCUGCUGCUGGCUGGGGUGGCCACCUUUUAUUCCCUUAUUUGUCCCUGCCCAUGUCCUGCUGAUUGCUCCAUUUUACAGAGUGCUGAUUGGUCCAUUUUACAGAGUGCUGAUUGGUGCAUUUACAAUCCUUUAGCUAGACACAGAGUGCCGAUUGGUGAGUUUUUACAGUGCUGAUUGGUGCAUUUACAAUCCUUUAGCUAGACACAGAACACUGACUGGUGCAUUUAUAAUCCUCUAGCUAGAAAGAAAAGUUCUCCAAGUCCCCACUAGACCCAGGAAGUCCAGCUGGCUUCACCUCUCACUGGGACUACAGGUGCACACCACCACACCCAGCUAAUUUUUGUAUUUUUAGUAGAGACGGGGUUUCACCAUGUUGUUCAGGAUGGUCUCGAACUCUUGAUCUCGUGAUCUGCCCGCCUCGGCCUCCCAAAGUGCUGGGAUUACAGUUGUGAGCCACCACGCCCGGCCCUAGCUUUUCCUUUCUGUUGCAAGUCCUCUCAACUAGUGUUGCCUUCCACCCUACAAAGCAGAAUUACCUCAGAAGUCCUAUGGCCCUGACUCUAUCUAUGUCUGCACAAAGCACUACUGUGCUUUGCUGUCUGCAAGAACAGAGAUUGUUUGCUUCAACCACUUUCUCUGAAUGGAUGAAUGAGUUAUGAUGAUAUCUAAAGUUACCCAAUUUCAAGCAAGAGGAAGAAUCUGGCUCGGUACCACAGAUGUUCUUGGAAUUGGGAUAGUAAAAAAGUCCCUGAGGCAUCCCUUGGUCUGCUCUGACCACACUCUCUUCACAGGAAGAGGCUUGGGCCACAGCUCUGACUAUAACUCUGCUCUUCCUCCAAACACAGCUGAGGAAUUGGGUGGUGGGGCACCUGCUCCCAUGCUCUGUGGCCUGGCUCAGAGAGAAGAGUUGCCUUAAUUACAUUAUUAUUCUUCCUGGACAGGCUGUAGGUUGUGUAAAGUAACAAAAAGGACUGAGAAGUGACUUCCCAUUCAGCCUCUUCCAAGGCCAUUUUUGAUAGGCAGGUCAAAUUCACUCACAUUUGGUUAUUUGUUGGCCAGUCUAGUGCAUUCACCCUUGCUGGUCCUCAGUCAUGCUCCUUUACCUUUACAGAGCAUCCUAGACUGCUCUUCCUCUUACCUUCCUUGUGAAACCCACAACCCCUAGUCCCUCCCCUUCCCUGGCAUUUGUUAUGCCCUCUACCAAUCCCUGACCUGGUAUUGGUCAGUCUCCAAUCCUGGUGGAUCCCUGUGGGAACUAAGUUAAGUCUAACUUUUGUCUCCCUCUUUAGAAUUUACUGGGAGUACUGUAAAUAAACUAUUGUUGUUAUAAUUAUUUCUGAUUAACAUUUUUACACCUAACAAAGUCUCAGAGAGAUUGAAUUUACUGGGUUGAAGGGAGGAGCACCUUCCACAUGACCUGCCCAGCAAUUAAAGCCGCUUGUUAGUCCGAGGCCCAGGACGGCCGAGGACAGCUGGAGAGCUCUUCGUUGCAGGCAGCUCUGGUUAACAUCAACCGGGAAAGCUCUUUGUAAACACAUGAAUAAUUGAUCGUCCAGCGCUCACAUAGCUACCGCGGAUCUGAGCCCGUAUGACUCAUUUGCGAGCCAUUCCUGUCGUCUGGAUGCCAUAACAUUGGAGGAAUGAUGAUCGUUUCUUGGAGGUUCUUCUGUGGCCAGAGUUGCCAAGACCAAGGCUGUAAUGGUUUGUUAUGAUGACCUUUGUUAUUCCAUUAGGCUCAAUUGCUUUAAAAAAUGAUGUGUGCAUACUUUAGGAACGUUUUUACCCUUUAUGUUGACCUGACAUCAUAGUUUAUAUUAUAAAAUGUAUUAAUGACAGAAGAGUGUUUUCAUGUCCCAAGGACAAAUUUUAACAACCAUAAUCUGCCCUCAGUCAUCAUAAAUAUAAAUGUAUUGGUCAAACAGAUCUCGUUAAUGUGGCCAAGAUAAAUGCAAGUCUAUAUUUUAAGGCAGUCGAAGUCCUAGAGAAUAUAUCUGGAGCUUUUGUGGGGCUAAGAGAUCUUGUAUAUAUGCUAUCAAAAGGCUGAGAAAAUUAACAUGUUCCCCCCUCUGAUUUUGCAUUGGACAGAUAUAAAUGUCUUGGGGAUGUCAAGUAAGAUUGUUCACAUAGUUUCUGGACACCAUUAAUGCCUGAUGGGGUGAAUCUUAGUUCUUAAAGCUAUAUUCUGCUCAUUAUGCUCACAGGGCUUUUGAAAAGAGAACAAAAUAAAGAUUUCAAGUCUUAGCAA